AGGUCUGGGCGCUGAUCUUGUGGUUGAAGAAACCAGCUCUGGGGAAGGGUCUCGGGCGCGGGCGGGAGGGCACCUGUCAGGGUCCCUGGGAGAGGCAGCCCUCGGAUCUGCCCCUGCCCACCUCACGCUGCGUUCCAUGCUGGCCCCAGGCGAUGUCAGUCCUGCUGCAGGCCAGGACUAGUUCCACGGCCCUGAGCAUGCGUUAGCCCCUUCUUGCCUCCAUGCCUCAGUUUACCUCGGAGUGAGCUGCGGGAGACGUCUCCCUGCCUGGCCGGGGCGGCUCUGUCGUAGCGGAGGGCAGCGGUACGAGCCGGCCGCGGGCUCGGGGUGUCCCAGGUGGUGCAGAGCCGGAGCCGGAGCCGGAGCCGCGCCGCGCCGCACCAUGGCGCCCACCCUGGCCACUGCCCAUCGGCGCCGCUGGUGGAUGGCCUGCACGGCCGUGCUGGAGAACCUCCUCUUCUCGGCAGUCCUCCUGGGCUGGGGCUCGCUGCUCAUCAUGCUCAAGUCAGAGGGCUUUUACUCCUACCUGUGUACCGAGCCAGAGAAUGUCACCAAUGGCACAGUGGGCGGCACAGCAGAGCCGGGGCACGAGGAGGUGAGCUGGAUGAACGGCUGGCUCAGCUGCCAGGCCCAGGACGAGAUGCUAAAUUUGGCCUUCACUGUGGGCUCCUUUCUGCUCAGUGCCAUCACCCUGCCCCUGGGUAUCGUCAUGGACAAGUAUGGCCCGAGGAAGCUCAGGCUGCUGGGCAGCGCCUGCUUCGCGGUUUCCUGCUUGCUGAUUGCGUACGGAGCAAGUAAACCAAACGCUCUCUCCGUGCUCAUCUUCAUCGCCCUGGCUCUGAAUGGCUUUGGUGGGAUGUGUAUGACCUUCACCUCAUUAACACUGCCCAACAUGUUCGGCGACCUUCGGUCCACGUUUAUUGCCUUGAUGAUUGGGUCCUACGCCUCCUCGGCAGUCACCUUUCCAGGAAUCAAGCUCAUCUAUGAUGCUGGUGUCUCCUUCAUCGUCGUCCUCGUGGUCUGGGCCGGCUGCUCCGGGCUGGUUUUCCUCAACUGCUUCUUUAACUGGCCCCUUGAGCCCUUCCCGGGGCCGGAGGACAUGGACUACUCGGUGAAGAUCAAGUUCAGCUGGCUGGGCUUUGACCACAAGAUCACAGGGAAGCAGUUCUACAAGCAGGUGACCACGGUGGGCCGGCGCCUGAGUGUGGGCAGCUCCAUGAGGAGUGCCAAGGAGCAGGUGGCGCUGCAGGAGGGCCACAAGCUGUGCCUGUCCACCGUCGACCUGGAGGUGAAGUGCCAGCCGGAUGCCGCAGUGGCCCCCUCCUUCAUGCACAGCGUGUUCAGCCCCAUCCUGCUGCUCAGCCUGGUCACCAUGUGCGUCACGCAGCUGCGGCUCAUCUUCUACAUGGGGGCUAUGAACAACAUCCUCAAGUUCCUGGUCAGCGGCGACCAGAAGACAGUGAUGGCCACGGUUGGCCUCUACACCUCCAUCUUCGGCGUGCUCCAGCUGCUGUGCCUGCUGACGGCCCCCGUCAUUGGCUACAUCAUGGACUGGAGGCUGAAGGAGUGUGAAGACGCCUCCGAGGAGCCCGAGGAGAAAGACGCCAACCAAGGCGAGAAGAAAAAGAAGAAGCGGGACCGGCAGAUCCAGAAGAUCACUAAUGCCAUGCGGGCCUUCGCCUUCACCAACCUGCUGCUCGUGGGCUUUGGGGUGACCUGCCUCAUUCCCAACCUGCCUCUCCAGAUCCUCUCCUUCAUCCUGCACACAAUCGUGCGAGGAUUCAUCCACUCCGCUGUCGGGGGCCUGUACGCUGCCGUGUACCCCUCCACCCAGUUCGGCAGCCUCACGGGACUGCAGUCUCUGAUCAGCGCGCUCUUCGCCCUUCUGCAGCAGCCGCUGUUUCUGGCCAUGAUGGGUCCUCUCCAGGGAGACCCUCUGUGGGUGAACGUGGGGCUGCUCCUUCUCAGCCUGCUGGGCUUCUGCCUCCCGCUCUACCUGAUCUGCUACCGGCGCCAGCUGGAGCGGCAGCUGCAGCAGAGGCAGGAGGAUGACAAACUCUUCCUCAAAAUCAACGGCUCGUCCAACCAGGAGGCCUUCGUGUAGUGGCUGCCGCCUCGGAACUGCGGUCUCCUGCCUGUGCUUCAGUGACUGACCCCUGUCCUGCCCCUCCAGAGUACCCCACGCACCCCCAGGACCUUCGCCGUCUCCGUGCCAGCGUUCACGCUCCCUCCCGGGGCCCUGCCUCGGAGCUCUGUGGUGGAAGGACGGGAGAGGGCCCCGGACACGCGCGUUUUCUCCUGCCGAACGCAGGGGCUGCCCUGACUUUGCUCUGCCGCCCCCCGGGGACCCGGGGCCUGGGGUCUCUGUGGUGCCUGCAGCAGGAGCCAGGAACGCCCGGCAGGCAGGCGCUCUCCCGCCAGUGUCUGGAUUCUGCCUCUUGCCAAAGCAGAGGGGGCUGCCAUCCCCUGCCUGCCACCUGCCCCUCGGCUGCAUGCCCACAGCCGUACCUGCCUGAGGACAAAGGCUUGCACUGUCUCGCCCGCGCCUGGCCCCCACCCCCUCCCCGGCCAGCCUGAGGCUGCCUGAGGAAGGAAGGACCCGCUUCCUGUUGUCGGUGCUAAUUCCUUUGUAAUUCCAGCCCCCUGUCGCCUGUCCAGGGCCUGCCCACCCGUUGGAGGCCGGUGGAGAAGCCCCACCUGGCUUAUGCCCUGGAGAGGGUUUAGCGGGCUGGGUGGACCCCUCGCCUCCUCCCCGAGGGCCAAUGCCGCGGACACGUUUUCACUGUCACCCUCGUUCUGUCUGCCACCUGAAGGGAAUUUGAGGACCGCCGCCAGGGCACCCCGUACAUACACACAGCUGCUUUUGUGGAGGUGGACGAAAGGCUGUGGCCGGCAGACGUGGAGGUCCAGGCCGGGGUGGGGACGUGGGUGGGUCCGAGGUGUGUGUGGGGUCGGGGUGGGCUCUAGGAGUUAGCCCUUAUCCCCACUGACCAGGCGGGAGCCGCCAGGCCUGCAGCUGGGCCAGUGCCCAGGAGCCAUCCUGGCGUGGGGCCAGGAGCUUGUCCAAGGCCACAGGCCCACAGCACCCCCUGCCGGCGGGCUCCGUGGGGCCCUGGAGCUGAUGACGGGGGAGGCCCGUCCGCCUGGCCCACCAACCCGCCCACCUUGACUGCCCCCAGAAGUGUGUCUUGAGACCUCCUGGGCGUGCUUAGAGGGGUGAGUUGUGUUUGGAUUUUUAGUUAUUUUCUCUUCAGUUUUAUUAGACUUCUUUUUUAUAAAGCAAUAAAUCCAUUUUCCUCCGGGUAAGGGAUGCCCCUUCUGGCAUAUCAGUUAAUAGCUGCAUGUGCCUAUUUUGAGCUUGAGAAGAAAAGGCAGGACAAGAUUCUCUGCCACCGACCAGCUCCAGCCGUGCCCAGCUGCUCUUCGUCUCUCUGGGGGACUGCUGACUCGGGAGGGACAGUGGGCCAGGAAAAGACCUUCCUCCCCAACCCCCAAACAAACUGGGCUUGUGCAGACAUCUUAGAAGUGUGAGCCACCCUCCUCUACCGAUUUUCCCAGCCAAACAGGCGAAUCCUGGUCCCUUUCCAUCCCUACACCCUUCCACAACCCUGAAGAUUCCCGCUGGGUUCUUCUGCAGGCUCAGAGCAGUUCAGGAUGUGGGCGGCAGGGAGGGGGAUGAAAGGAGAAGAGGAAAGGGCAGGUCCAGGCCACAUUCAAGCUCCACAUUAACAGCUUGGGCGCCUGGAACACAUAUCUCCUAGGCUUUAUUUCACUCAAAUAUUUAAAAAAAGACUGGGCGUGGUGGCUCACGCCUAUAAUCCCAGCACUUUGGGAGGCCAAGGCAGGAGGCUCACCUGAGGUCAGGAGUUCGAGACCAUCCUGACCAACAUGGAGAAACCCCGUCUGUACUAAAAAUAAACAUUAAUCGGGCGUGGUGGCGUGCGCCUGUAAUCCCAACUACUCGGGAGCCUGAGGCAGGAGAAUCGCUUGAACCGGGGAGACGGAGAUUGCCGUGAGUCGAGAUCGCACCAUUGCACUCCAGCCUGGGCAACAGAGCGAGGCUCCGUCUCAAAAAGAAAAAAAAAAAGAGAACGAGAUAAACAUGCCCACUCCUGAGAACACUCGUUUUGUGAUGUUAGUGGUUAUUCUGAUUUUCAAGAAAGUAUUAUAGUCAAGUUUGGGAAAGGCUGAGUUAAAAGUCAAGCCUGUUUCCUUACAGCCAGCACUGACAGCACUUUGCCAACGCUCAUGAGCUCCGUGGCUCCUCAGGAGCGGGUGUGCUGUGCUGCCGAGGAACGGCUCGAACCAUCAGAGCCACCAGCCUCCACGUGCGGCUCCAUGAUCACCCCCAGCAGAGGCUCCCGGGUGCUGGUUCCAAAUGGAGACUCCAGGUCUUGCCGCUGACCGGUGACUCUGCUGCCAGCAUUUGAGACCCGCCAUCACACAGGAGUUGCAGAUUCGGAGAAACCCUAACUAGCCAGGGUGCUGCCAGCUGGGAAAAGGCCGCCUUUUUUUUUUUUUUUUUUUUUUUGAGUUGGGGUCUUGCUCUGCCAUCCAGGCUGGAGUGCAGUGGUGCAACUGAUAGCUCACCACGGCCUCCAACUCAUGGGCUCAAGGGAUCCUCCCACCUCGGCCUCCUAAGUAUCUGGGACUAUAAGUGUGUGCCACCAUGCCUGGCUAAUUUUUUUUUUCUUUUUCAUAAAGAUGAAUUCUUGCUAUUUUGCCCAGGCUGGUCUGGAACUCCUGGGCUGAAGCAAUUCUCCCACCUCAGCCUCCCAAAGUGCUGAGAUUACAGGCGUGAGUCACAAUGCCUAGCCAAAAAGCCAGUCUUGAGAUGGGGAAGACGUGGCCCGUGCUGUCCCCAGCAGUGCCCAGUCCCAGCCAAAGUGGGCAGUGCUGCCUCACUCUCCCACCCACCCUCAGGGUGUGGCACUUACUGGGAAGAAGCAGGCAUUGAGAAACAGAAUUGAGGGGGGGAAACAGUCCAGGGCCAACAGUGCUUGGGGAUUGAGGCCUGAAAAUGCGAGCAGGGUACAGAGGCUGUGGCUGGCCAGAUGGGUCGGGUGCCCCCUGCACUCCCACCCCCUAGUCAGGGGUCACCCAUCCUACUUUGCCUUGUGUGGAGCUGACAGGUGACAUGUUUUCCUAUUGUUGUCCUUGACUUGAUAACAAUCUGGGAGUUAAACACAUAUGAUCAUCCCUGCUUUACAACUGAAAAACGAGGCCUAGAGAUACUAUCAUCAUAUACACCUGAAAAACGAGGCCUGGAGCGAUGGAGGAGCUUGUUCAAGGUCAGAGCCAGCACUCAUAUAUGGGUCUUAAGACACUGGAGCAGCCAAGGGCCUCUAGACCAGGACAUUCCACUCGGAGCAGCAGCUCAGGGGCCACCAGGCCUCUGUGGCAGGGGGACCUCUGUGGCAGGGGGGACCUCUGUGGCGGGGGGGGGGCCUCUGUGGCAGGGGGGUCACAGCCCAAGGAAGGGGAGCAGGCCCAGGCAUGGUUUCCGUUUCUGGGAGCCAAGAGCCUUCUCAGAAGAGGGGGAGAGAGCUACUGCAUGGAAUCAUUUGGGCCCUGGAGGCUGAUGGGUACUUGGGGGAGCAAUCCCUGGUGACCCCAACCAGCAAGACAAGUGCCCUGUGAAGGGGAAGGGACUACAGCUGAUCAAAGGAGCAGGCACCAGUGGCCGGGCCUCCCGUCUGCCCCUCAUCCUCCAGGCUCUGGCGGGAAGGAGCAGGAAGGGCUCCCUGCCCUUGGGGUUUUGAUCAGUGAGGAGGGGGGCUUGGGUCUGAGUCUGGGUCUGGGUCUGCUGCCGAAACACUGCCCCCAGUCCCUCUCCUCACUAGACUCUGGGGUCUAGGCGUGUCUUUGUGGUCGGCCUUCUCCAAACCCUCUAGGCCUCUGUCUGCAGCUGCUGCUGCCUGGACCUAUACACAAGGUCCCACCCCUCACCGGGGCCAAAGACGUGGUUGCAGGCCCUGGUGGAUCCUUUCUGUUUUGCUCCAUCCCCGUCCCCUCUUGCACCCAGCAUCGUCCUGGUCAGAACUUCCGUUUAAACCUUCCUUGCCUGCCGUGCACUCCGAGGGGGGCGUCACUUUGCCAUAGGCCCCAGGGCUGAAAAUGGCGGGACAUCCAGUAUUGGGCUCACGUGCAUAAGACUGUCCCAGACAGCAGCACAAUCACGUUCAGCCAAGUGGAGUUUCCGACGCACUUGUGUGGCAGCCGCGUGAAUGUGAGCCGAUAUGCAGCUGGGAGGGGUUGUGGGCCUCCUGCGGUGAGGGGCUCCUGCCAGGAGCUCUGAGAAGCCUCCACAGAAUCAGCCGUCGGGCUCCUUCAGCAGCAGCUCCCCUUAUCUGUGCCAACGACUGGGGGCCUAACUCAAGGGUGCCAGCCCGUCUUCCGCCAAUACAGACUGUGGGAUUCUGAGAGUUAGGAGCCUGGGGUCCCCUGGGGUGGGGUGGUCAGGGUGAGCAGGUGGGCUCUGUGAGCCUGUUUCCCCAUGCCCUGACUCACCCCAAUCCCUGGGUGAGGACAGAGCUCCUGAAGGCCACUGAAGGAGGUGCAGCACACUCCACCUGGGUGGCCUUCCGCAGCUCAGCCCUCUUCCUGCCAGCAGGAAGCCUCUGCCUGUGCUCCUUAAGUUAGCCAUCCUCACCCCCUCCGGGCAGCUCUGAGACUGAGCCAGGGCCACUAGCAGCACCCAGACCUCGACCCUUCUCAGACCGAGGCGCCACCACCCCAGGCCGAGGAGGCAAGGAGGGAAGACCAAAGUCUAGAGGACUGUCUUGGUGGCCCUGGGCGAGUCUUGAACUUUGGUGCCAUCAUCUGCAAAAGGGAGGAAAGAAUGCCUGCGUGGUGCAGCUACGUGGAUACGCAGUGAAGACCCGCAUGGUGGGACGCCUGGCACUUAACAAUGGUAGCAUUUGGCCGGGCGCGGUGGCUCACGCCUGUAAUCCCAGCACUUUGGGAGGCCGAGGCGGGCGGAUCACGAGGUCAGGAGAUCAAGACCAUCCCGGCUAAAACGGUGAAACCCCGUCUCUACUAAAAAUACAAAAAAUUAGCCGGGCGUAGUGGCGGGCGCCUGUAGUCCCAGCUACUUGGGAGGCUGAGGCAGGAGAAUGGUGUGAACCCGGGAGGCGGAGCUUGCAGUGAGCCGAGAUCCCGCCACUGCACUCCAGCCUGGGCGACAGAGCGAGACUCCGUCUCAAAAAAAAAAAAAAAAACAAUGGUAGCAUCGUUUUCAGUGCCCAGGAAGAAGGCAGCUGGGACAGGGAAAGGGCCACCACACCACACCCAAGCCCAUACAACAGGAGAGCCACUUUCAGCAGCUCUGAGCAGGACAGACUUGUGGCCAAGUCAAGAAAGUAAGGUCUGGUCCCAGCGAGGUGGCUCAUCCCUGUAAUCCCAGUGCUUUGGGAGGCCGAAGCGGGGGCGGGGUGGAUCACUUGAGGUCAGGGGUUUGAGACCAGCCUGACCAACAUGGUGAAACCUCAACUCUACUAAAAAUACAAAAAUUAGGGCCGGGCGCAGUGGCUCACGCCUGUAAUCCCAGCACUUUGGGAGGCUGAGGCGGGCGGAUCACAAGGUCAGGAGAUCGAGACCAACGUGGCUAACACAGUGAAACCCCAUCUCUACUAAAAAUACGAAAAAAAAAAAUUAGCUGGGCGUGGUGGUGGGUACCUGUAGUCCCAGCUACUUGGGAGGCUGAGGCAGGAGAAUGGCAUGAACCCGGGAGGUGAAGCUUGCAGUGAGCCGAGAUUGUGCCACUGCACUCCAGCCUGGGCGACAGAGCAAGACUCCGUCUCAAAAAAAAAAAAAAAAAAAAAAAAAGUAAGGUCUGUAUCUGCUGACCCCACCCUUCUCCGAAGCCCUCUCCGAGCAAAGCCUUAAGAAACUCUUCUCUCGUUCACUUUUCUUUUGUGGCUUUCACGUUUUGGUAAGACUUGGCCAAAUAGCUGCUCGAGAUAAUCAAUCACUGGUGGACAAGUUUCUGCUGAGUGAGGUUUCUGCUGAGUGGGGCGACUCAAGGCACGGUCACGUAGGCAGCACCUGUACACCGCAUCCUCAUACAGCUGCGGGACCGUGCCUCUGACUGUGUGCGUGUGUGUUUAUCUAAGUGUGAGAUGCAUCCGGGCAUGUCAGGGUGUGUACAUGUUGGGAAGACUGUGUAGAUUUCUUGUGUGCCGCUCUCUGAAUGGAGGAGAGGGGAAGCGUCUUACCUCGCUGAAUCCCUUUCCAUUGCUGGAAAGAACACCUGGGCAGGAGCGGCCCCAAGACCCCGCCCAGGCCCUCGGAAGGGAGCCUGAAGGGUUAAUCCGUACCCUGUAUUAACCAGGGUCAACCCAGCGGCUGACCCGCCUCUUCCCUGCUCCUUUGCCGUUUCUAGCACCUGGCUUACUUCCUGGCACACAGUGAGCACUCAAUAAAUGUAUGCUGAGAAUGA